GGAUUUGCCCGGAGGCCGCACCCGCCUCCGGCGGGGCUCUCAGUGAAAAAUGUACUCUGACCUGAAUCCUGAAUUUUCCUUGAUGGUCAAAAGAUUAAGAAAUCAUGAGUGGAGGAUCUCAAGUCCACAUUUUUUGGGGUGCUCCAAUUGCUCCACUGAAAAUCACAGUAUCAGAAGACACAGCUUCUUUAAUGUCUGUUGCUGACCCCUGGAAAAAAAUUCAGCUUUUAUACAGUCAACAUUCUUUAUAUCUGAAGGAUGAAAAACAGCACAAAAAUCUUGAAAACUAUAAAGUCCCAGAAUCUAUUGGUUCUCCAGAUCUUAGUGGUCAUUUCUUAGCAAACUGUAUGAAUAGACAUGUUCAUGUGAAAGAUGACUUUGUACGUUCUGUUUCUGAAACACAGAAUAUAGAAUCCCAGAAGAUUCACUCCUCUAGACUGAGUGAUAUAACUAGCUCUAAUAUGCAAAUAUGUGGAUUUAAAAGCACAGUUCCGCAUUUCACCGAAGAAGAAAAGUAUCAAAAGCUUCUCAGUGAAAAUAAAAUUAGAGAUGAACAGCCUAAACAUCAGCCAGAUAUAUGUGAUGUUGUUAUUCAUGAGGACCAAUGGAUUGGCGAGACAGUACUACAAUCAACAUUUAGCAGUCAGUUAUUAAAUCUUGGGAGUUAUUCAUCUAUUCAGCCUGAAGAAUAUUCCAGUGUAGUUAGUGAAGUUGUACUUCAAGACUUACUGGCAUAUGUGUCCUCAAAACAUUCCUACCUCAGAGAUCUUCCUCCGAGGCAGCCUCAGAGGGUGAACAGUAUAGACUUUGUAGAAUUGGAGCACCUUCAACCUGAUGUAUUAGUCCACGCAGUACUAAGAGUUGUUGAUUUCACUAUACUGACAGAGGCAGUAUACAGUUAUAGAGGACAGAAGCAGAAAAAAGUUAUGUUAACAGUGGAACAGGCCCAAGAUCAACAUUAUGCGCUUGUAUUAUGGGGUCCUGGAGCAGCCUGGUACCCUCAACUUCAAAGGAAAAAAGGUUAUAUUUGGGAAUUUAAAUAUCUUUUUGUUCAGUGCAAUUACACACUAGAAAACCUAGAAUUGCAUACAACGCCUUGGUCAUCCUGUGAGUGCUUGUUUGAUGAUGAUAUAAGGGCAAUUACAUUUAAAGCAAAAUUUCAAAAAAGUGCACCCUCCUUUGUGAAGAUAUCAGACUUAGCAACCCACCUAGAGGAUAAGUGUUCAGGAGUGGUUCUGAUUAAAGCCCAGAUUUCAGAGCUGGCAUUUCCUAUUACAGCAUCUCAGAAGAUAGCGCUAAAUGCUCACAGUUCUCUGAAGAGUAUUUUUUCUUCUCUUCCCAACAUCGUAUAUACUGGUUGUGCAAAAUGUGGAUUGGAACUAGAAACAGAUGAGAACAGGAUCUACAAACAAUGUUUUAGCUGCUUGCCAUUUACUAUGAAGAAAAUAUAUUAUAGGCCAGCGUUAAUGACUGCCAUUGAUGGAAGACAUGAUGUUUGUAUCCGUGUAGAAUCAAAGCUGAUAGAGAAGAUUCUUCUCAACAUUUCUGCAGACUGCCUCAACAGAGUGAUAGAUGGAGUUUUGCUCUUGUUGCCUAGACUGGAGUGCUGUGGUGCGAUCUCAGUUCACCAUAACCUCUGCCUCCUGGAUUCAAGCAAGUCUCCUGCCUCAGUUUCGCAAGUAGCUGGGAUUACAGGCAUGCGCCACCAUGCCCGGCUAAUUUUGUAUUUUUAGUAGAUAUGGGGUUUCUCUAUGUUAGUUAGGCUGGUCUUGAACUCCCAACCUCAGGUGAUCUGCCUGCCUUGGUCUCCCAAAGUGCUGGGAUUACAGGCGUGAGCCACCGUGUCCGGCCUAUCUCUUCUUUUUUGCAUAAUGUAAAUUAGUCUUUAUCUCUUAGAGAAGCAUCAUUCUCAUAUCACAUAUACUUCAGUGUUUUGUCCAUUCUUGAGACAAUUAAAGUUGUACUACUUGGCAUUAAUUAGAUUGUGAUCAUAAGUCAAAAUGUCAUUGGUUAUAAAGUGGUCAUCAGACCAUGCAGACUAUUACUAAUAUUGGUUAUGUUUUAGUUUAUUGCAGUGAAAAUACAAAAUUUAAAAGUUAUUGUAGAGAAUUAUCAUACCCCCCAAAAUAUGUCAUUGGUCCUCCAGGACUCUGUAGUCCCCAUCCAAGAAAGACUGUGAUAAUUGUCAAGGGGUUAGUACGGUCUGAGCAUGGUUGAUGGUGCUCUGUCAUUCUGGUAUUGAACAACCUGCCAAAUGUCUUGAUUACAUGUCCUAAAAAAGUGAGGGGAAGAGUGUAGGACAAAUGCAAAAUAAAAUAACACAUUUAGCUAUACUUUUAGUAUUUUUUAUUAUUGAGAUUCAAUAUUUAAGUGACCGAUUCAAGAUUCUUUUAUAUAAAAAAUGAAUAUAUGCAUAAGUAACUGUGAUAAGAACUGUGGAUGGAUAAGAGCACUUUUCUGAUGUACUGCAGCAUAACCAGAACUGCUGUCGGUCUGAACGGUGUGUUAUCUGGGCCUGUUUCUUGUGUCAGGGGGAUCACAUGCCGUCACUCUGGAGUGCCUCAAUAGCUUGUAACUAGAAAGAGAAGGUAUAGAAAGAGUAGUUUACUUACCUGUUUAUUUAUUUAGAGACAGAGUCUUGCUCUGUUGCCCAGGCUGGAGUGCAGUGGCACAAUCUCAGCUCAUUGCAAUCUCUACCUCCUGGGUUCAAGCAAAUCUCCUGCCUCAGCUUCCCGAGUAGCUGGGAUUACAGGCAUGUGCCACCACUCCCGGCUAAUUUUUGUAUUUUUAGUAGAGACAGGGUUUUACUGUGUUGGCCAGGCAUGUCUCGCACUCCUGACCUCAAGUAAUCCGGCUGCCUCCGUCUCCCAGAGUGCUGGGAUUACAGGUGUGAGCCACCGCUACUGGACGGGAGGAGAAAUUUAAAAUGGGUUUGAGACUUGAGGAACCAAAAGAAACAAUGAAACCAUUCAAUGUGUGUGCUCCUGUCAAGCUAGCAGCGAUCUUGGGAGCUCUGUGUUUUUGUCUUUUGCAGUUCCUUCCUCAGAGAUCACCUAUGGGAUGGUCGUGGCAGACCUGUUCCACUCCUUGUUGGCAGUCAGCGCAGAACCUUGUGUAUUAAAGAUUCAGAGCCUUUUUGUGUUAGAUGAAAACAGCUAUCCAUUACAACAAGAUUUCUCCCUCCUGGAUUUUUAUCCUGACAUUGUAAAGCAUGGAGCCAAUGCCCGUCUCUGAGGCCAGAGGAAGAAAUUGCAGGCAUUUCAAGGAAGAAGUACUGAAAUGAUUUGUCUUUUGAAAUAAAUGAAUGACAGGGCUUUUGCUUUGGAUUUUUUAUGAAAUAUAUUUUACAAAGAGAAUUGCACUAGAUAUAUAAAUUAAAACUUUUUUCUAAGAAAAUCCUGUGAGGUUUAAAAAGAUUGUUUUUGUCUUUUGGUUUCUUACUUUCUCCUGGAGAAAUGAUCUACCAGUCAAGGCAAUAUGUAGCAGAUCCCUGGGAAUUAAAGGUUUGCCCAUUUGUUCACUGUAUUUAGUCCCUGCUACAUUCCAGGCAUUGUACUAAGUAUGGGGAACCACAGAGAAGACAUUCCCUCAGAAACUGCUGCAGUGCUUUCGCUUAUCCCUACCUAAAAAACCGUCAAUGUGAAAUCAUUUCCUUGAUUAUAACUAUAAUGAUAAUGGAUUAGUUUAUAUAAACCUAUGUUUAGACAAGUUCAAGACAAGCGUGUCUUUCUAUAAAAAGUAUUGAAAAUGAAGGAAAUGAGAUCAUGUUUCAAUUUAUUAAAGCAGGGAAGAGCGUUCUGUGCUUAGUUCGUGUCUAGGAUUUGAGUGCCUUACUGAAUGCAUUUACCAGCAAACAUGUAGCAAUCUGUUCUCUCAUUGUGAUUGUGGAAGAAGCUCAUGUAAAAUGAUAGUCAUUAAUGAGGAAGUAUGGCGUGGUACUUAUUCUGUAAGUUCAGAGUAUGCUGAGUGUUAAUAGAUUAUCAUAUUGCCUGAAAAUAAAUUCAUGAUGACAUGAA